UUGCACCACUGCACUCCAGCCUGGUGACAGAGCAAGACUCUGCCUCAAAAAAUAAAAAAUAAUAAACUGAGGAAAAAUGGCAUAUUAGUUAAGAUGAUUUUUUGCAACUGACAGAUUCUGCAAAAGAGGGACUUUAAGAUCAUUUAUGGAAGAAUUGAACAUGAGGCUACAGGAAGGGCGGUGAUGUAGCGAUGCUUCUGCUAAAUAGAGCCUGUGACUCCAAAAUCAUCAGGACUCUAGUCUCUGCUUCUCUGUGCCUCCAUUCUCUUAUCAUUCUAUAUUUCCAGGAUAAGAAGCUUGGCUGCCAACAACUCCCUAACAUGGGAGCUACAUUUUAUAGUACCAAACACUGGAAAAACUGGCUUGACUCUCUCUUUCUACCUCCAAAAAAUCUCUGUCUUUCUCUCUUUCUCUUCUCUCUCAUGCACGCCAGUUGGGCUUGAACUCUGCAAUCAAAUUACCUGAAUUCAGAUAAUUGAGAGAGAGAGAAUAUGGAAGAGAGAGAAAGAGGAGAUGUGACAUGGCAUACCAUAGGAGUGGCAAAUAGUUCAGCACAUGACUGACGAUAGAUUUAUGGAUGAGAGUGAUGGGAAUUGAGACAGGAAGAGUUGGUUCAGGUUGAGCUAUUAAGAUCCUAGAAUAUCCUCAUAAGGAGUUUAGAUUCUGUCCUGUGGCUGGUGGAUUUCAUCUAAAAUUUAAGCUUAUAUAAAUAUAUAUUUAUAAUUAUAUAAUUAUAAAUAUAUAAUUAUAUUAUUAAUAUUUAAUAUCAUAAAGGAAGCUCUGACUGUGUGUGUAACUGGGAUGAUGGUAAAAAAGAUAAUCAGGCAGCUCUCUGUGAUAACAUACAAACUGUAGCAGAAAAAGGACUUCUGGAUCAAGAAUAUUGGGAAAGGCUACUUUGCUACCAUUUUCAUCAUUGCAGUCCUCCUUAUUUAAAGCUAUGGAAGAAGCUUUUUUUAGUAACCACAAGAUAGCAUACUUCAUCUACAGAAGUAUAGGUCUGGUUAUUUUAAGAACAUAUGGAUUUGAUCUUUGCCCUAAGUCUAAUAUAGUAUCUUUACAUAAAAAUCUGUAUAACUGCAUGUACACUUUAUUUUUUGUGGGAUUAAAUUUUGUUAAAAAUCAUGGUCCAAAAUGUUUACUAUCUGGAAAAUUGGAGAUUUAUUUCUCCUUACACUCCUCCCGUAUACACAGCACAUGUAUAUUUCUCAGCUUCAUAUUUUUAGUCUUUAAUGAUUGAAUAAUUCAGUAAUAUCAUUUAUCAUGAUAAAUUUGAACUAAGUAGGUAUUUGCAAGUAUUGUUAAUAAAAAAUAGUCUAUACUCAGAAUAUCUCACAAUGUAUAAUAUAGAACAGUAACUCACCCCUUUUACAUUAAUUUAUUUUUUGAGGUGCAUUAAUGUACUAUGUCAUUUUUUUAGUAUCCACUGCCAUAGUUCUGUGACAUUUAGACACAGAAUUAGACAAAUCUAAUUUUAUUGUAGUCCCAAAAGGCUUAAUGUUUGAUCACCCUUCCCUUUCCUUACCAAGUUCCCCUAUCUUCUCUCUCUCAUAUACAUACACAUAAUAUUCCCACAUAAACAAUUUUUUUGGGUGAGAUGUUCUCAUUCUAUUGAGUAGAUAAGAAAUGUAGAAUAAGGACACUGCAGGCAUGAAGAAAAGAAGUAGGGAUUUAACAGUUGGUGCUAAAAAAAUAACAGAGAUGCUCAUUUACUACCCCUCUUGUCCUGGCUCCCAGCAUUCUUUGAAACAAUUUAGGUGGGCCUGACAGUAAUUCCCUGAAAGUGUGCUCCCCUUCUGUACCACCCACCAACCACAACUCAGAUCGUAUUUGACUGUUUUGUGACAUCUCUUCUUAUUUCUCACUCAAGGUUAUACUUGAGGUUGAUUUCAGUUAGAUUUCUACUGUGAAAAUGCUAUGAAUAUGGGUCAGGAAUAAGUCCUGUGUUCUCAUUCAUUAAAAAUUUGGGCUAUGAGAUCAAGAAAAAUCAUUGAGCCAUCAUGGUGAUGCUAACCAGUUCUUGUUUUUCUUUUGUGAUUUGGAAUUUUGAAGCAUGGGACAUUCAGAACUGGGAAGGACUUAAUACAGACUCAUGAAAGUUCUUUAAUCUUAUCAAGACUAUACUGUUGCCAUCUGUGAUACUGAUAACUAGCCUAUAAUGAGUGCCUGCUACGUGCCAGGCACUGCGCUAAGAAUUUUGCACACAUGAUUGAUAAUCACUACAUUAAUAACAAGUUUUAAGAUAAAAUUGGCUGCAGCAUUGGCAAGAUGUCGAAUCAAGCAUGAUGCCCUUUCAAUUUACCACAUCCUUCCAGAAACAGUUAGGAAACAGGAACUAAGGGCCUCCACUUUACCACUUUAUGCUUGGAUAAAUACUUGUAAAAUCAGCCCUGAAGAAGUUUAUAAUAAUUUGAAGAGAAGAGGCUAUAAUAAAGUCAAAUCUGUAUUGCAUAUUGAUGAUAAAGUCUUUGCUGUGGAUCAACAUUGCUAUGAUGUCUUAAUUUUUCCAUCUCAUCUUAAAAAUGAUCUUAUAAAUAUAGAUCUUUUCAAAGAUUACAAACUUAUAUUUCAGGACAAAUCUCGAAGUCUUGCUGUCCAUUCUGUAAAGGCUUUAUUAAAUAUGGAUGAUGAUGUCUUAAUGGUCAAUACAGGCUCAUGGUACACAGUUUCCCACAUGUCAAUUUUAACAAAUAAUAAUACCUCAAAAGUAUUUGUGUGUGGAGUACAAUCACAAGCUAAGGAUCCUGACUUGAAGACCCUUUUCACAAAAAUAGGAUGUAAAAAUAUUGAAAUACUUCAUGAGAAAUUUAUUAACAUUGAAUCAAAGGAUCACAGGUUACAGAAAGUUAAAGUGAUUUUGCUGCUACCUCGUUGUUCAGGACUGGGUGUUAGUAAUCCAGUAGAAUUUAUUUUAAAUGAACAUGAAGAUACAGAAUUCCUUAAAGAUCACUCUCAAGGAGGCAUCUCAGUGGACAAACUUCACGUUCUUGCUCAACAGCAGUAUGAACAGCUAACACAUGCAAUGAAAUUUACUAAAGCUCAAGCAGUUGUUUACUGCACAUGUUCAGUUUUUCCAGAAGAAAAUGAAGCUGUUGUUAAGAAAGCACUGGAAUUUCAAGACCUUGGGAAUAAAGGACAACCUUACAGGCUUAGUCCUCCUGUUCUUCCACUGUGCUCCUUAAAGGAAAUUCAAUUGUCUACUGAUAAAUUUUUCAGAAUGGAACCAUCUGAAAUUACCAAUGGUUGUUUUCUUUCUAUUUUAACAAGGGAGCGGGACCCUUCUGAGACAGUGUCUGUGAAUGAUGUUUUGGCCCGAGCUGCAGCCAAGGGUCUGCUGGAUGGGAUUGAGUUGGGUAAAUCAUCAAAACGGGAGAAGAAGAAGAAAAAAUCAAAAACAUCAUUGACAAAAGGUGCCACUACUGAUAAUGGCAUCCAAAUGAAAAUUGCUGAGUUCCUGAAUCGAGAAACUAAAGCCAGUGCUAAUCUAUCAGAGACUGUAACAAAACCACCUCUUCCCCAGAAAAAUACUGCUCAAGUGGGGGCUUCCUCACAGACCAGAAAACCCAACAAGCUGGCCCCCCAUCCUGCAGUGCCUGCAUUUGUGAAGAACACUUGUCCCUCCAGACCGCGUGAACGGCAGACACACUUCUUAAGACCUCGGCCAGAAGACAGAAUGGUUGCUCUGAAACCCAUCAAGAUUGUUCUGCCUCCAGUCUUUAUGCCAUUUUCAAGUCCCCAAGGGAUCAGAUCUCGGAUGCCAACUCAACAUUUGUACUGUCGUUGGGUUGCACCCAAGGCACUUGUGCCCACCUGCCUUCCCACACACUCACUAUCCAGAAAAGAGGAAAAGCCUAAAGAUGACACACCUUCCUCCCUACUCAGGCCUCCUCGGCGAUGGCUUUGAUUGUCUUGUGUUUUUUAUAGGGGCCAAAGAGCAGUUGAUUUUUUUUCAAAGUCUAGUAUUUCUCUGAAGAUUCUACAUCUCUACACAAGAUAUUCAUUCUUUUGGUCACCUAGGGAUCUUCUAAGUGUGAUAUUACUUUCAGAGAAUUCAGACAAGUGAGAAACAAUAAUGUAGGAGUCAGCAAAGCAGAAUUCAGAGACUUCAGCCAAUCACUGCUGCUCUGAGAGGAUCCAGUUAGAGACUCAGUAUCAGCGGUCAGAACUUAUCUCACUCCUGUGAACUUUCAGGCUGGACUUAAAGCUGCCAAGUUUCCCCUGCAGGGAAGGAAACACUGCCUCCCUUCAGCAGGUAGCUCAUUAGAAAGCCAAACAGGCAAACGAUCCUGGCCUCUCCCGCCAGCUGACCGCUCUUCAGCAUCCAUGCGGUUGUAGUCGUGACUUUCUCAGUCACGAUCAAGGGUGAUUUUUUCUUAAAUAUCAAGCUGUUCUUUGAACAGGGAAUGAACAUGAGUUUUUGUAACGUGACUGAAGUUGAGUUUAAGUAGGAAGCGCAGGAAGUUCCCAAGUGCCAGGUGUGUGUAGCUCAGAGUUCCUUUUACAGUGAGGUGUCUCUCACUGGGGGAGCUUCCAGGAUCCUGAGCAGACUGGACACAAUCAUCUCUCCCUUCCUCUAUGUCAAGCACUGUUACAAAAGACUGUGAGCAAAUUUCCAUCUAAAUAUUAAUAAUUCUGAAGAAGAGGCAAAACUGUUGAAUGCAAGCGAUACCUAUUGUUGAAGAAACCCACAAAUUUCUGAUUCUAAGAUCAGGGGAUACAACAAAAUCUACAAGUCAUUUCAAAUAGCACACAGGAAUCAAACUUUGGUAAAUCAUUUCUGAGGCACAAUUAAAUAUAUUGUAGCACUAUGUUAAUUAAUUAUAUUAAAUGUCGAUUCAUCUUGAAUGUAUUCUCAAUUGCCUACCAAAAAUUGGUAUGAUUAUCAUUUCUGGGUCUACUGAUUUUUCAUCAUGGCAACAGAAAUUGUCAUUAAAUAGAAUUAAGAUACAACUAUAUAUCUUAUUAUUUAAAAACAUUCAUAGACAUAUUCAUAAAGUUUGAAUUUAAAGUUUUAUUUUUGCAAUUCAGUUGUAUAGAAAUGUUACAUAAAUUCCUAAAUGCUCAAUUCAGGUGGCAUGAUUUUUAGAAUAUUAUCUUCUUCAAGAUGAAUACUUAGGUCUACUUCAGCUCUGAUAUUCUAUUUUUACUUUCUUACUUGAAGUGAGAAAAGAGAAUGGUGAAUUGUAUUAUAGCGGUAAUACAUUAUUUUUAUUUUAGCUUAGAUUUACAUUUAUCAGUAAAACGUGUCAGUGGGCUGGGUGCAGUGGCUCACAUCUGUAAUCUCAGCAGUUUGGGAGGCUGAGGUGGGCACGCCACUUGAGCACCGGAGUUCCAGACGAGCCUGGACAACAUGGCGAAACCCCAAAACCCCAUCUCUACAAAAAAUACAAAAAUUAGCUGGGUGUGGUGGGACACGCCUGUAGUCCCAGCUACUUAGGAGGCUGAGGUACGAGGAUCUCUUGAGUCCAGGAGGUGCAGGUUGCAGUGAGCCAAUAUUGCCCCACUGCACUCCAGCCUGGGAAGCAGAGUGAGACCUUGCCUCAAAAAAAAAAAAAAAAAAAAAAAAGUGUCAAUGAAGAAAGGAAACAAGACUUUUUAUAGUUGAACCAGGCUUAUUGUAUUUUAAAUCCCUGAAGAAGAAUUCUUCAUGUUAUCACUCUUGUACAGAAAGAUAUAAAGUGCUCAGCUUAUUUUGCUGAUUUUGAAAAUCAAACACUAUCUCCUUGCCCUAAAAUUAUAGCGUGUGGCUCAUCCUCUUAUCCCACCCAGAUUUCUAUCUGGUUGGUUAGGGUAGUCCAUGCCUCAAGGAAGGCGGUGCAGCUUAAUUUAACAUAUUGUUCAGUAAAGAAUCCCAUUGUGUAUCAUAAGAAUCCCUUAUCCUUUUCGGGCCCUCCACCAUACCAGACUGAAAAGUAUUCCAUUGUCCAGAAGUAGCUGGUCUUGAGAUUUUUAUUUUCAAGUGUAUUUUCUGUGAUGUUGUCUCAUUGUUAUGGAAUAGUUUAGGAUAAUUUUCUGAUCUCUACAGUAGCAUGUGAAGUCACAAUUUGUUGCCACUUACAUUGAUUAUCUCCUAACAUGCAUUUGGCACUAAAUUAUUUUUCUCUUUAGAAGUAUAUGAAGAUUCUGAAUUAAACCAUUCAUUAAUUACA